GCCGGGAUGUUUUUAGGCAUUUACAAGUCAGUAACAAUCCCUCUUUCUUUCUCCUUUUUCACCCCAAGGGUGGCCUACUCUCCAGGCUGCUGAGAAUCUUGCUUUUCUUCAUUUAAGCUUUAUCUCAAACAUCAUUCCAUAUCAAUUCAUUCUUUUUUAUAGCUGCAUGUCCCCCAGCACAGAUUUUUUUUUUUAAAACACACCCUUAAAAUCCAGGGCUUACCACCUGGGUCCAAAUCAGAUGUCUCCUACUCUGAUUCACCCAUGUCCACUGCCCACCCCAUGGACCUCGGACCACAGAGUCUGGAGGCUGCGGUCUCUUCUUACUGGGAGUUAGAUUUCUACCCUGUGUCUGAUGUUAUGGGGUAGGAGCUGGGGCUUAUGCCUCCUCUCUGGAGAUGGGGAGGCCACAUCAGAUCCCAUAGCUGAAGUCUUUACCAAACAGGUGCUGCCAUGCGGGCACUUAGGUGAACACGAGAAGCCUCGUUCUAGAACAAUGAGUCACAGCCUGCUUGUUUAGCCAUCCAGCCCAGGUGCCACCGCCUUCUUCCCUCCACAGCUGCAGGUUUAUUUGCUUCUGUCUCUGAAGAGGUGAGGUAAGGUGUUGUUCUUGGAGGAAGAAGCUAGGAGCGUAGAGUAAGACCUGGAUGUAGAAACGGCUGCUGGAGGACAGGACCUGUGGUGGGUGGAGGUGGUGAGGGGGCAGUGGCACCUGGACGGAGCAGACCCACCUUAGCCUGUGUGGGGUGCGGUUUCCCUGCUGGCUGGCUCUGGGGACCCCCCGGCUGUUGCCACAGAGAGGAAAGACCUGUGGCCUCAGAUUCAGACAGCCUGAGCUUGUCCCCACAACUUAUUGCUGGGAGAUCUCGGGUCUCCAGCCACCUGCCCUUCCCGAGAAGAGAGAGCUCUGGGCCUUCUUCCUGCCAGUCUGGUCUUCGAGUGCGUUCAGGACAGAUAGACCUUGGCACAGGCUGCCCCGAGAUUCCUGCGACGCUGUCUGUUCCUGCCUUCUGUGGAGCAUGGCACCCACAGGCUUCCAGGACGGAUCAUAGACCCGAGCCUCCAGGAGGGCGCCCUGUGCGGCUCACUGCGCGGUCCCUCUCAGCUCCCCUGCCACCCAGCCUCUGAGGCCGGCUCCUGUCCCGGAAAUGCCCUCGGGCACCUGGAUGAGGCCAUCCCAGAGCGGGACCCAACUGUGCCACCCACCAAGCCUCCCCCUGCGCCCCCCGUGCCCUCGCAUGUCCGGCUGCCAGGGCAGACUGUAGAAUGUCUGUGCCCCAGAUCCACGUGGAAGAAGUGGGUGCAGAAGAGGGGGCGGGAGCAGCCGCACCACCCGAUGACCACCUCCGGAGCCUGAAGGCCCUCACCGAGAAACUGAGGCUGGAGACCCGCAGGCCCUCCUACCUGGAAUGGCAGGCCAGGCUGGAGGAGCAUACCUGGCCCUUCCCGAGGCCGGCUGCGGAGCCACAGGCGAGCUUGGAGGAGGGGGAGCGUGGGGGGCAGGAGCCCUUGCUCCCCCUGAGAGAGGCUGGGCAGCACCCCCCUUCUGCCAGGAGUGCCAGCCAAGGUGCCAGACCCCUGUCCACUGGCAAGCUGGAAGGCUUUCAGAGCAUCGAUGAAGCUAUAGCCUGGCUCAGGAAGGAACUGACGGAGAUGCGGCUGCAGGACCAGCAACUGGCCAGACAGCUCAUGCGCCUGCGUGGCGACAUCAACAAGCUGAAAAUCGAACACACCUGCCGCCUCCACAGGAGGAUGCUCAACGAUGCCACCUACGAGCUGGAGGAGCGGGAUGAGCUGGCCGACCUCUUCUGUGACUCCCCUCUUGCCUCCUCCUUCAGCCUCUCCACACCACUCAAGCUUAUUGGCGUGACCAAGAUGAACAUCAACUCUCGGAGGUUCUCUCUCUGCUGAGGAGCCCUCAGACUGGGCGGAGGGGCUGGAGCGGAGGGCUUGGGCUGGAGGGGUGUCAGAGGAAGCUGAGGCCAAGUUACUCCAGUGGGUCUCCCGGAGGCAGGGGUCCCUGGGACUGGCGACUCAAGGGCCCCAGGACCUAUUCAGUGGUGCUCUCCCACCCAGGGGCCCUGGGUGUGGAUGCCAGUGUCUCUGUGACUGGCUCUUGCUUACUACCCAAAGAGCUCUGCAGAAGGGCCGCUCCAACCAAGAUGUUAAAGGAGACCUGGGUUCCCACCAUAAUCCAUCCCUCCACGGUCACGUUCCUGUUUCCUGGAAUCACUGGUGCUAUGAACUGGGAUUCCCAAAGGGAGGCCCCCCAACAAAGCUGUCAUUUUUGCAGAAGGCUGUCCCGCAAGGGCCUUGGGGGAAAUUAGGCAUGUCAGAUGUGCCUGUCUCACGUGCUGUUGCUGUCCUCUAAGUAUUGUCUCAAAUUCACCCUAAGUACAUGACUCAGCAACAUUGACAGGGAGCUACUAGGAAGGGAAAAUCGAAAGGCAUGACAAAUGGGCACUUGGGGACGCAGCCCCAGUGGCUGGCAGCCAGUGUCUCUGGUGAGCCUGACACUAUAAGGCUGUGUAAAUUGUAAAUUCUGGCGUGUGCUGGGACAUGUGAUGGGGGCACUAGCGUAGCUUGGGUGCAACAAGCACAGAUGUCCCCAUUGUCUCCCCUGGCCACAUGCAUCUCCAAAGAGCCUCUUCACUGCCACCCACACCCCAGGGUGACAGCCUGGGAGACCACUGGUGACUGAACCAGGCAGGUCCUGAAAGCAUUUUCCAUAACUGAAUUCUCCUGCAGGGGCGUGACCGGGGCCUCCUGGUGGAUUCUGGUGGUGUCACCUUACUGCCCUCUCUGGAAAGACAAUCUAGGGAGCCCAGAGGCCCAUCCUGAGCCUCCUCUGAGAUUUUGUGCCUGACCUAAACAACUAGUUUUAAUAAGACUGUUACUGAUGUGUUGUUCACUUGUUAGUAACUGAUUUUUGUCCAAAUGCGGAAGCCACUUGUGUAGGUCAACUACAGUGCGUAGGAUUUGAUUUUAAGAGUUUCUCCCUCCCAACAGGCUUGAGGAUCAGCAAGUUAAGACCCCAGCAGGUUAGGGAGGUCAGUCUGGGGUCAUACGGCAUGGCAGGGGUCCCUCGGCCAGACCCGUAGAAUCCUGAGAUAAGGAGUGUUUCUGACCUUUGGUGUCAUCUAGUCGAGUCCUCUCAUUAGUAAAGGAGCAAAGUGAAACCUGGGGGAGGAGAAGGACUUCCCUCAGGUUGCACAGCUGUUUAGGCUAUAGAAUAUUGAUGUGUGAAACCAUUAUUGAUAAUGCCUAGUAGAUCACAUGUCAAUGAACUUGAACCCCAAAGAUGGUCGUGAUGCUUUGCCAAACCCGCACACUGCCAACCCCUCUACUCUCCACCUCAGCCCCCACCCACAUCUCCCAGAGUAUUGCAAUUCAGAACAUUUGGGUCAAGGUGGAGCAAGGCACUGACAGUGGCCCCACAGGGCAUGUGUCACUAAUCACUGUCCCAUGGUCUACGCACGGCAUCUGGCUGCUCUGUCUACUGUGACUUCUUCCUGUGUAAUCUCAGUGGGGCCCGUGUCCACCCACACAUCGUGACCCACAUAGGGGAGAGGUUGCUUUUCUUUUGUGGGCUGAGAGUAGGACAAUGCAAAUGAAUGAUCUCUAGUAGACAGAAAAGAACUUGGUCUCUUUUUUAAAAUUUCAAAGAGCCAGAAGUUCUAUGCCUCCUUCAAAGUAGGCAGAACAACGCAGCCAAGAUCUACUGUCUGCCAUGCUCUGUGCAAUGAAGUCUGCAGGCCUGAGGACCAUGUACUGCUGUCCUUCCUCAGAGCUCUGCACAAACACUGCCAAGUCCUGAAGACGCAUUCCUUUCCUGCCAACCUCUUUCCAGAUAAGCCCUUGAGGUCUCGGGCUGACCUACACACACACACACACACACACACACACACACCCCCACACACACACACACGACAGAGAACAUGCCAUAAACAUCCUUGAACCCAUGCAGGAAAGCCCAUCCCAUAUUCUGAAAAAAUGCCAAAUUAGGUUUUUCUUUCUUUUUGGAAAUCAGUCAUUACAGUAACCGAAACCAUUGGGUUCAGCGAAAAUGGAAAGAUUUAGCUGAAUGUAGUCAGUCCAAUUAAGUUGGAUGCAACUGAGUGAUUUAGUUGCUUGGGUAACCCAGUGCUUGCUUGCUUUCUUCAUUCUCUGGGUGGAAACUAAGAUCAAGACACAUGUUUGGGGAUAAGUUAAAUGUCUGAGCUAUUUUGCUCGGUUUAUCCUAAGAGAACUUUAUUAUGGGAUGAGGAGGUGACCCAAGAUGAGAAGUGGAGGGGGACAGCGAUGUUUUCUAAACAUCGUCCAGUGUUGACUGGCUUCCUUACUUUGCACAGUGAACACAACUAACCACAUUAAUUCAGCUUUGUGAAGUCCCUGCUCUCUGUGGGUCUAUGAGUCAGCAGCAACAUUGGCCUAACCUCCGUCCCAGCCUCCUGGCUCACCACAUGUGUACAGUGCUGUUUGCAGUUGUACUCAUUAUCCAUCCAUCUCUCUGCCAUCCCCAAGCAUCGCUGGGUGUAAAACGCAAACUCUCCACCGACACUGCCAUGCGUGGUCAUGUCUUGAUGCCUUCAGGGGCUCAGUAGCUAUCAAAGAGGCCUGGAGGGCCUGGGCAGGCUUGACGAUGCCUGACCGAGUUCAAGACCCACACCCUGUAGCAAUACCAAGUGCUAUUACAUAAUCAAUGGACGAUUUAUACUUUUAUUUUUUAUGAUUAUUUGUUUCUAUAUUGCUGUUAGAAAAAGUGAAAUAAAAAUACUUCAAAAGAAGAUAUCCAUAUAAAAAUAAAA